ACUCGGCCGGCAGCGGAGCCGCAGCCACCAGCCGCCCGCGCCCUCCAGCCCCGUCCGGGAGUCCCCGGCCCGCUGCGGUGCCUGGCUGAGAACUGUGUCUUCCUGGAGACUAGGCUGGCAUUUUGACUUUGGGGUUGCUGAAAAGCCAGGAGUCAAAAUGACUGAGCGCUUUGACUGCCACCAUUGCAACGAAUCUCUCUUUGGCAAGAAGUACAUCCUGCGGGAGGAGAGCCCCUACUGCGUGGUGUGCUUUGAGACCCUGUUCGCCAACACCUGCGAGGAGUGUGGGAAGCCCAUCGGCUGUGACUGCAAGGCAUGCUGAUGUGCUCUUUCCUCCAUCUGGGGACUUAAUGACCGGAGCACUGGCUGUGGUGACAUCUAGUGGCUUUGCUUUCCUGUUGACCUUGGAGAUUUCUCUCUCAGUUUUUCUUGAAGGACUUGUCUUACAAGGACCGGCACUGGCAUGAAGCCUGUUUCCACUGCUCGCAGUGCAGAAACUCACUGGUGGACAAGCCCUUUGCUGCCAAGGAGGACCAGCUGCUCUGUACAGACUGCUAUUCCAACGAGUACUCAUCCAAGUGCCAGGAAUGCAAGAAGACCAUCAUGCCAGGUACCCGCAAGAUGGAGUACAAGGGCAGCAGCUGGCAUGAGACCUGCUUCAUCUGCCACCGCUGCCAGCAGCCAAUUGGAACCAAGAGUUUCAUCCCCAAAGACAAUCAGAAUUUCUGUGUGCCCUGCUAUGAGAAACAACAUGCCAUGCAGUGCGUUCAGUGCAAAAAGCCCAUCACCACGGGAGGGGUCACUUACCGGGAGCAGCCCUGGCACAAGGAGUGCUUCGUGUGCACCGCCUGCAGGAAGCAGCUGUCUGGGCAGCGCUUCACAGCUCGCGAUGACUUUGCCUACUGCCUGAACUGCUUCUGUGACUUGUAUGCCAAGAAGUGUGCUGGGUGCACCAACCCCAUCAGCGGACUUGGUGGCACAAAAUACAUCUCCUUUGAGGAACGGCAGUGGCAUAACGACUGCUUUAACUGUAAGAAGUGCUCCCUCUCACUGGUGGGGCGUGGCUUCCUCACAGAGAGGGACGACAUCCUGUGCCCCGACUGUGGGAAAGACAUCUGAAUUCAACACAGAGAAGUUGCUGCUUGUGAUCUCACACACAGAUUUUUAUGUUUUCUUUCUCACCCAGGCAAUCUUGCCUUCUGGUUUCUUCCAGCCACAUUGAGACUUUCUUCUAGUGCUUUUCAGUGAUACUCACGUUUGCUUAAACCCUUUAGUGCUUUGUGAUAGUUCAGUCCCAGGGAAAGAGAAAACUCGCCCUAGGCCCUAGGUGGGAAGAUGGUUUGAAAUUUUUGUAAUCGAGUAAGGCACACCCAAAUGUAAAAAUCCUUUUGAAUGAUGCCUUUAUAAAUCUUUCUCUCACUGUCUAUUUAAGUGCAAUUAACAUAUGUCACGAACUUGAAAGUUUUCUAAACUCAAUAAGGUAAUGACCAGUUGUUAUUUACAGCUCUGUAACCUCCCGUUGCGUCAAGUCUAAACCAAGAUUAUGUGACUUGCAAUAAAGUUAUUCAGAACAGAAUCUUUUGCCAGGCACAGAGUGUGAAAUCAUGAUUACAGGUCGAGGCACUGAGUCUAAGUAACACUUUAUUGCAUGGUCCCAUGGUCACUGUAUGAAGUGCAGUUCCAAUGUUCCAAUGGCCUGGGGCAUUGCCAACUGGAACAGCAUCACACCCUUUAAAGGAAGCCUUCGGCUGGGCACGGUGGCUCACGCCUGUAAUCCCAGCACUUUGGGAGGCCAAGGCGGGUGGAUCAUGAGGUCAGGAGAUCAAGACCAUCCUGGCUAACAUGGUGAAACCCCGUCUCUACGAAAAAUACAAAAAAUUAGCCGGGUGUGGUGGUGAGCGCCUGUAGUCCCAGCUACUCGGGAGGCUGAGGCAGGAGAAUGGCAUGAACCCGGGAGGCAGAGCUUGCAGUGAGCUGAGAUGGCACCACUGAACUCCAGCCUGGAAGACAAAGAGACUCCGUCUCAAAAAAAAAAAGCCUUCAGUCAGCACCAGGCACCUCUUCCUUGCUACCUUCUCUCCCUUUUUUUUUUUUUUUUUUGAGACAGAGUCUCGCUCUGUCGCCCAGGCUAAAGUGCAAUGGCACAAUCUCAGCUCACUGCAACCUCCACUUCCCGCGUUCAAGCGAUUCUCCUGCCCUCAGCCUCCUGAGUAGCUGGGAUUACAGGCACCCACCAUUAUGCCCGGCUAAUUUUUGUAUUUUUAGUAGAGAUGGGGUUUCACCAUGUUAGGCUGGUCUUGAACUCCUGACCUCAGGUGAUCCACCUGCCUCGGUCCCCCAAAGUGCUGGGAUUAUAGGCAUGAGCCACCGCACCCAGCUACCUUCUCUGUCUUUCCCAUACUCUUUCUCUUGGAAUGUAAUCCUCUGCAUUUGACACAGUAACAUAAACUGACAGUGAAGCCAAUUUUCAGGUCAUUUUUCUUGGCAGAGCUUAUCGGCUCUGUCCCAGUGUUAUGGAUCCACAUCUUACACCGACUUCCAUAAAGUGAAAGAUUGCACAAGGACAUAAGCAACUUGAGGCCAGAGACGACAUCCUGUUCAUCUUUAUGUUCUCAACACCCUCGCAACUGAGGGCACACUGGGAGCCUUCAGUGUUUCUGAAAAGGGCAGUAAAGCAGGAGAGACACACAGUCAUUACAGUAAAAAUAACAUUCUGAGCUACUAGUGUGGCAGUAGUCUGUGGAAUAAUCUCAGAUAGCAGUAUACAGUUGGGAAGCACGGAGCCAAUGUAUGGGAUAGAACAUUGCACAGUUCUCUUUAGAAUGGGAGCAUCAGUGACCUUUUUGUCCUUAGUUUUCUAAGACAAUGCAAUAUAAUAAAAUGAUAGGCUGAGCAACAGAAAAAUUUGGUGGAAAUCAAGUCUGAUAUAUGCUGAGCAUAUGUGAAAUCAGUUUCUUAAUCUGAGUGUUAGUCACUGUUAGAAUGUUUGAUAAUGUCUGGAAUGAGUCUUUUGGUUUUAUAGUUGACUUGAGGUUUUGCUUAAAAAGAAUAAUUUCAUCCUUUGUUAGUUGUUUUGCUGUUUUCUACUUCAUAAUAUAAAAGUAAAAGCACUCCAAAUUUCAUUUUGGAACAUCUUACUUGUUCCUCAUUAAAACCAUAGACUCUCCCAACCUUAAAUUACCCAUUCUAAAAUUAAUGGUUAGGGGGAAUUCCACUUCUAGUAAAUAGCUCCAAUUGGACUAAUUCUCCUCCAAAUUAACAGUCAUUCUGGACAAAAUAUUUAUUUAAUUGUUAAGAACACUGGAGCACGAUCCAAAGCAGGCAGAUAUUGGAGGGCAGUAGACACUUGGAAGAAGAGAACGACACUGGGUGAUUUUCCUGUUUCGGCCUUUUAUCCAAUGGCAGGCCCCCGCCAGGGAUCUAAAACUCUGUUAGGAAACCUGCAGUCUUACUGGCCUGAGGAACCAGAGGCCAGAGUUCGGGACAAACAGCCUCUGGAAAGUGAGGAAGAAAAUCCUGAAAAGGAGAGCCCCAAGUUCGUCGCAUGAACUUAGAAAUUUCUGGCUGACAACUGAACCGUGUAUACUUAGGCCAGACUCCAAGCAGCCCAGCCAAGGCUAAAAGCAUUGACUGACAGGACUUUACAGAUAGUGGUUUGCAGGGCUUAGCUGACCGACCCUCUUCCUACUGAAGGAAAUUACUUGUAUAUAAACCACACAACACAAAGUCUCUGAAAAUUUCCCCAGAAGCAUACAACAAAUAAACAUUCAUUCAGGAAAAUCCACUACUAAGUCUUAGAAAGAACAGUGAGUCUGUGGCAUUUGAGCCACAGCCUCAUCCUAUCCCAUCCCCACUCCCCAGCUUCAUGUGACAAACUCUAUUCUGGACCAAUGCAGCCAAAAAUUAAGGGGUCUCUCUUCCUCCAGCUACCAGUCUAGGGCUUUGCCCCAGGUGCGACAGGCUGAGAAUCGUAGAGCUCCAAUUGCCCCUACCCUAGCCUGCUUAGUGCGGAGGCUCCACAUUGGGAGGGGCAAUCUGAGAAGACCAGCGGCUAUCAACCCACUCACAGAGAAGGGAUGUCAGUCCUGGAGAAGCAGGCUGCUGUCCAGCCCCCAGAGGAGAUCCAGGCUCUGAGACUGGUAACCCAGCAGUUAUGCCCAAGGGGACUGGUAUUUGGUACGGAGAACGAGAAAUCUUUGCCUAAGGGGAUUGUCAAAAACAAUAAGACAUCUUACCAGUGAGCCAUUAAGGAAGGGGCUGGUAACUCCAUGCUAUUAGUAGCAAAAAGCAAAAUGACAGACCAGCCAGAAGUUUAACACAGAAAACCAGAGAAAGAGAUAGCCAAGAAGAGCCCUCCUGGAAUCUGGUUUAUCCUUGAGGUUCGGGAAGUAUGUAUGGACAGGGCUGUAUCCACUCAGGAGCAAUCAGAUGUGAAACAAACUUGAAAGCAUUCUCUAAGGCAUACACAGAUCCAUCAGCAAAGAGCAGAAAUCUUAUUAGCUCAAAGUGCUUAAGCAGAACCUCUGACCAAACACUGGCUGAACACAUAAAUGUGUUUGUUCAAAGAACUAAAGGAAAUCAUAUUUAAAAAAGGAAGGUAAAGGAACAAUUACAGUUGUUCCUCCAUAUCCAUGGAUUCCUCAUCUGUGGAUUCAACCAACUGUGGAUCAAAAGUAUUUAGGAAAAAAAA